ACCAGUGGUGCCUCAAGACCCACCGGGGAGAGGCUUAUCUUAACUCCAGCUGCCGAAUGAGAAUGAGUUUGAAGCUUUUUGCAGGAUCAUGGAACAGAGCCUCCAUGCAAUAGUGCAUCCUGAGGUAAACUGUUACCUGAGUAAGGGCUUUAAGUAAUGCAUUUCCUGGGAACGACAGUUGUGACAGAAGAGAAUGCUGGAACCCGUAGCAAGAUUCCUGUCUGAGAUGGAAAGAUGUCUCACUAUCAUUUUAUCAAGUGCUGUUGCUUUCAGCUAUGUAACGUUUUUCGAUCCCAUGAGAUGGAAAUCGACCAGUGCUUGCUAGAGUCCCUUCCCCUUGGCCAACGGCAGCGUCUAGUGAAGCGCAUGCGCUGUGAGCAAAUCAAAGCCUACUAUGAGCGCGAGAAGGCUUUUCAGAAGCAGGAAGGGUUCCUGAAAAGGCUGAAGCAUGCGAAGAAUCCGAAAGUUCACUUCAACCUCACGGACAUGCUACAGGACGCGAUUAUCCACCACAAUGACAAAGAAGUGCUUCGGCUCCUGAAGGAGGGGGCAGACCCCCACACCCUCGUCUCCUCGGGAGGGUCCCUGCUCCAUCUGAGAGAGAUUAGUAUGUUAUCUGAAGGAAAAGGAAAUGAGAAGGUAAACGAUGAAGUAG